UCUCUACCUGGAAAUUGGUACAGAGAUUCAGAGUCUUUGUCCAGGAAGACACUUUGGAGUAGAAGAAUGAUACCCAUCCAACUCACUGUCUUCUUCAUGAUCAUCUAUGUGCUUGAGUCCUUGACAAUUAUUGUGCAGAGCAGCCUAAUUGUUGCAGUGCUGGGCAGAGAAUGGCUGCAAGUCAGAAGGCUGAUGCCUGUGGACAUGAUUCUCAUCAGCCUGGGCAUCUCUCGCUUCUGUCUACAGUGGGCAUCAAUGCUGAACAAUUUUUGCUCCUAUUUUAAUUUGAAUUAUGUACUUUGCAACUUAACAAUCACCUGGGAAUUUUUUAAUAUCCUUACAUUCUGGUUAAACAGCUUGCUUACCGUGUUCUACUGCAUCAAGGUCUCUUCUUUCACCCAUCACAUCUUUCUCUGGCUGAGGUGGAGAAUUUUGAGGUUGUUUCCCUGGAUAUUACUGGGUUCUCUGAUGAUUACUUGUGUAACAAUCAUCCCUUCAGCUAUUGGGAAUUACAUUCAAAUUCAGUUACUCACCAUGGAGCAUCUACCAAGAAACAGCACUGUAACUGACAAACUUGAAAAUUUUCAUCAGUAUCAGUUCCAGGCUCAUACAGUUGCAUUGGUUAUUCCUUUCAUCCUGUUCCUGGCCUCCACCAUCUUUCUCAUGGCAUCACUGACCAAGCAGAUACAACAUCAUAGCACUGGUCACUGCAAUCCAAGCAUGAAAGCGCGCUUCACUGCCCUGAGGUCCCUUGCCGUCUUAUUUAUUGUGUUUACCUCUUACUUUCUAACCAUACUCAUCACCAUUAUAGGUACUCUAUUUGAUAAGAGAUGUUGGUUAUGGGUCUGGGAAGCUUUUGUCUAUGCUUUCAUCUUAAUGCAUUCCACUUCACUGAUGCUGAGCAGCCCUACGUUGAAAAGGAUUCUAAAGGGAAAGUGCUAGGCCUAGAGGUUGCCUGAGGCACAGGAUAAAAGACUCCCGAGCAAUUGAUAUAAUU